GUCAUCGUUGUGAGCCCGCUAUCAGCGGCCAGCGCGGGCGCGGCCGGAGACCGUGGGGCCCCCGGUUGCCGCCCCCUCGGGUAAGGCCCUCUGCUUCUCACUCUUCGGCCCUUUUUCUCAUAGCCGUUUCUCUGUUCUUCCUCUUUGCGUUGCUCUGCGGGCGCUACGCUGGCUCCACCGCCUUCUCUGCCGUUCAAACCCCGCGGUUGUCCUUACCCUAGCGAGGGUAGGGGGGUCGGGUGCCAUCGUCUUUCCGACGGAGUGGAUAUUUGUCCCUCCUUGAACCACAUGGUACCUAAAGGUGCUGGUGUCUGUGAUCCCUGGAGACAGGAGGGAAUGCUGGAUGAUCCCGACCAGCGGGAGCUUGGACAGCAGCCUGGUUUAAGCAAGGGAUGUCUUGGGCCCUGCCCCUGAACUAGGAGCCACCAUGUUGGUGAUACCCCCCGGACUGAGCGAGGAAGAGGAGGCUCUGCAGAAGAAAUUCAACAAGCUCAAGAAAAAGAAAAAGGCAUUGCUGGCUCUGAAGAAGCAAAGUAGCAGCAGCACAACCAGCCAAGGUGGUGUCAAACGCUCACUAUCAGAGCAGCCUGUCAUGGACACAGCCACAGCAACAGAGCAGGCAAAGCAGCUGGUGAAGUCAGGAGCCAUCAGUGCCAUCAAGGCUGAGACCAAGAACUCAGGCUUCAAGCGUUCUCGAACCCUUGAGGGGAAGUUAAAGGACCCCGAGAAGGGACCAGUCCCCACUUUCCAGCCGUUCCAGAGGAGCAUAUCUGCUGAUGAUGACCUGCAAGAGUCAUCCAGACGUCCCCAGAGGAAAUCUCUGUAUGAGAGCUUUGUGUCUUCUAGUGAUCGACUUCGAGAACUAGGACCAGAUGGAGAAGAGGCAGAGGGCCCAGGGGCUGGUGAUGGUCCCCCUCGAAGCUUUGACUGGGGCUAUGAAGAACGCAGUGGUGCCCACUCCUCAGCCUCCCCUCCCCGAAGCCGCAGCCGGGACCGCAGCCAUGAGAGGAACCGGGACAGAGACCGAGAUCGGGAGCGGGAUCGAGACCGGGAUCGAGACAGAGACAGAGAGCGGGACAGGGAUCGGGAUCGGGAUCGAGAUCGAGACCGGGAACGGGACAGGGAUCGGGAGCGGGAUCGAGACCGAGACCGAGAGGGUCCUUUCCGCAGGUCGGAUUCAUUCCCUGAACGGCGAGCCCCUAGGAAAGGGAAUACUCUCUAUGUAUAUGGAGAAGACAUGACACCCACCCUUCUCCGUGGGGCCUUCUCUCCUUUUGGAAACAUCAUUGACCUCUCCAUGGACCCACCCAGAAACUGUGCCUUCGUCACCUAUGAAAAGAUGGAGUCAGCAGAUCAGGCCGUUGCUGAGCUCAACGGGACCCAGGUGGAGUCUGUACAGCUCAAAGUCAACAUAGCCCGAAAACAGCCCAUGCUGGAUGCCGCUACUGGCAAGUCUGUCUGGGGCUCCCUCGCUGUCCAGAACAGCCCUAAGGGUUGCCACCGGGACAAGAGGACCCAGAUUGUCUACAGUGAUGACGUCUACAAGGAAAACCUUGUGGAUGGCUUCUAGGGAACAGAGCUGGAUUCCUUGUGCCUCAUAUGCCCCAAUGCUGGUCUCAGUAAAACACUGAGGUGGAAGCUUACACAUCUCCCUCAGCCUCUGGUUUUUCAGCACUUGGGAUUGGGGUUAAACCUUUAAAAACGGCUGUCAGGUUUGAUCUCAGUGUAACAACAUGGCCAGUGCCUGUUCCCCACUCCCUUGCCCCAAAAGGAUCUGGAACACA